AGUGUGCCCGGCGCGGGUGAGGCGGAAGCGGCCGGGGCGGGGGCGCAGGCCCGGCAGCCGCAGGCCGGUGCGGGAUGCGCCCCGCAGCCGCGCCGCGUGCGCCCGGCAGAGGCGGCCCUGCGUGCCGUACGCUGCGUCCGGGGCGCGCCCGCCGCUAUUCGGGAAGCUAUUCAGCUUCCCGGGCUCAUUAGCAGUCGCGGUGUGCGGCUCGGCGCGGGCUCACAAAGAGCUCGGCCUCGCGGACUGAGCCGGCGGCAGCGGGGCGGGGACGGCGGCGUACCCGGGCAGCCCAGCGCCCUGGCCAGUCUCCUGAAUAUUUACGCGUUGCUGAAUCUCCUGUGGACAAACCACCAAUAGGCCAGGACUGUCCUGUGGACAGACGGGGUGAGCCUCUUCUUGUGUCUGGAGAUUCUGAAAAGAUUUGAUCACCAGGAGAUUUUUCGGGACAUUACCAAACCACUCAUUUUAGGGUUGAAAAGAGCCAGAUCAUUGGAGAAUCCCCACAGACUGACAGUUUUCCCUGAAUCGAUGCCUGCUUAUUGUGCUCAUGCAGGUAGCUCCUAUUCCAUCUCACUUCGCUGCAUGCAGCUCACAUAUUUCAGAUGAUCCACAAGAACAUUGGGAAGGACCUGCCAAAAUCCUGCCUUGCUAAAGUCCAGUGGCUGCCUCCGGGUGAUGAUGGCUGUGUGAACGACUGCCAUGGCCCACCGGAAGCUUGAGAGCGUGGGGAGCGGCAUGUUGGACCAUAGGGUGAGACCAGGUCCUGUCCCUCACAGCCAGGAGCCCGAGAGCGAGGACAUGGAGCUGCCCUUGGAGGGCUAUGUGCCCGAGGGCCUGGAGCUGGCUGCCCUGCGGCCAGAGAGCCCCGCGCCAGAGGAACAGGAGUGCCACAACCACAGCCCCGAUGGGGACUCCAGCUCUGACUACGUGAACAACACCUCUGAGGAGGAGGACUAUGACGAGGGCCUCCCUGAGGAGGAGGAGGGCAUCACCUACUACAUCCGCUACUGCCCUGAGGACGACAGCUACCUAGAGGGCAUGGACUGCAACGGGGAGGAGUACCUGGCCCACAGUGCACACCCUGUGGACACUGAUGAGUGCCAGGAGGCGGUGGAGGAGUGGACGGACUCGGCGGGCCCGCACCCCCACGGCCACGAGGCUGAAGGCAGCCAGGACUACCCAGACGGCCAACUGCCCAUUCCGGAGGAUGAGCCCUCCGUCCUUGAGGCCCAUGACCAGGAAGAAGAUGGUCACUACUGUGCCAGCAAAGAGGGCUACCAGGACUACUACCCCGAGGAGGCCAACGGGAACACCGGCGCCUCCCCCUACCGCCUGAGGCGUGGGGAUGGGGACCUGGAGGACCAGGAGGAGGACAUUGACCAGAUCGUGGCAGAGAUCAAGAUGAGUCUGAGCAUGACCAGCAUCACCAGCGCCAGUGAGGCCAGCCCCGAGCAUGGGCCUGAGCCAGGGCCUGAGGACUCUGUAGAGGCCUGCCCACCCAUCAAGGCCAGCUGCAGCCCCAGCAGGCACGAGGCGAGGCCCAAGUCGCUGAACCUCCUUCCCGAGGCCAAGCACCCCGGAGACCCCCAGAGAGGCUUCAAGCCCAAGACCAGGACCCCAGAAGAGAGGCUGAAGUGGCCCCACGAGCAGGUUUGCAAUGGUCUGGAGCAGCCAAGGAAGCAGCAGCGCUCUGAUCUCAAUGGACCUGUUGACAAUAACAACAUUCCAGAGACAAAGAAGGUGGCAUCAUUUCCAAGUUUUGUGGCUGUUCCAGGGCCCUGCGAACCAGAAGACCUCAUCGACGGGAUCAUCUUUGCUGCCAAUUACCUGGGGUCCACCCAGCUGCUAUCAGAACGGAACCCUUCCAAAAACAUCAGAAUGAUGCAAGCGCAGGAGGCCGUCAGCCGGGUCAAGAGGAUGCAAAAGGCUGCUAAGAUCAAGAAAAAAGCGAAUUCUGAGGGGGAUGCCCAGACGCUGACGGAAGUGGACCUCUUCAUUUCCACCCAGAGGAUCAAGGUUUUAAAUGCAGACACGCAGGAAACCAUGAUGGACCACGCCUUGCGUACCAUCUCCUACAUCGCCGACAUUGGGAACAUUGUAGUGCUGAUGGCCAGACGCCGCAUGCCCCGGUCAGCCUCUCAGGACUGCAUCGAGACCACGCCCGGGGCCCAGGAAGGCAAGAAGCAGUAUAAGAUGAUCUGCCAUGUGUUCGAGUCGGAGGAUGCCCAGCUCAUCGCCCAGUCUAUCGGCCAGGCCUUCAGCGUGGCCUACCAGGAGUUCCUGCGAGCCAAUGGCAUCAACCCCGAAGACUUGAGCCAGAAGGAAUACAGCGACAUCAUCAACACCCAGGAGAUGUACAACGACGACCUCAUCCACUUCUCAAACUCGGAGAACUGCAAGGAGCUGCAGCUGGAGAAGCACAAGGGCGAGAUCCUGGGCGUGGUGGUGGUGGAGUCGGGCUGGGGCUCCAUCCUGCCCACGGUGAUCCUGGCCAACAUGAUGAAUGGCGGCCCGGCUGCCCGCUCGGGGAAGCUGAGCAUCGGGGACCAGAUCAUGUCCAUCAAUGGCACCAGCCUGGUGGGGCUGCCCCUCGCCACCUGCCAAGGCAUCAUCAAGGGCCUGAAGAACCAGACACAGGUGAAGCUCAACAUUGUCAGCUGUCCCCCGGUCACCACGGUCCUUAUCAAGCGGCCAGACCUCAAGUACCAGCUGGGCUUCAGCGUGCAGAAUGGAAUUAUCUGCAGCCUCAUGAGAGGGGGCAUUGCUGAGCGAGGGGGCGUCCGUGUGGGCCACCGCAUCAUCGAGAUCAACGGGCAGAGCGUGGUGGCCACAGCCCACGAGAAGAUAGUCCAAGCUCUGUCCAACUCGGUCGGAGAGAUCCACAUGAAGACCAUGCCCGCCGCCAUGUUCAGGCUCCUCACGGGUCAGGAGACCCCGCUGUACAUCUAGGCCACCCCAGCCUGGCCACGCAGCCAGGACACCGGGCAGGGCCGCCCGGGCCCAGAGGAGCUGGGAGCCGGGCCGCAGACUUGACCCCGACGCCACAGCCCAGCCACGGACGCUGGCUCCCCAAAGGGUGUGCCCUCACCACCCACUUGAUUUUUUUCAUUUUGCCAAAAAGGGGUAUGUCUUUAUCAAAGGAGAGUCACAGAACAAAUGUUUGUUUGUAAAGCGUUCCAAGUAUUUUGCCACGUUCUGGACUGUCUUCUCCCUGCACAAGCCAGGGUGUGUCUCGGUAGCUGUGCGUGGUGUGGAGUGUGUGUCUUUCCUCCCUGAAGCUGUGCGGAGCGAACUGGCGCCUCCGAGGGACGCGGCUCCCGGGGCAGGGCAGCCGUCACCCCUGCCUCCCGCCCCCUUGGCUGGGACGUCUGGGGUCCUGUGGGGCCCCCACAAUGGUCCCAAACAGCUGCCUCUGCCACUGACUGCAGGGACACGGGCAGCCUGGCUCCCAGGACACGACUUGUAAUGAAAGUUUGGGGACAUGUGAUUGAUUGAUUGAUUGUAAAUAAAGGAUGAUGGCCACAACAUGAAAACUCCAUAUUUAUUUAGAUGCUAUUAUUACUGUUUGGACUUUUAUUUUGGCAGGCUUUUUUCCAGACUCUAGGGUUUUCCAAUGUGACUAAUGACCACACCUGCCUCUCCCGUCGUCUCUUCUGGGCACCCUCCCACCCGGCUGCAUACCCGGGCAGGGCUCCCACAGAGACAAGGAGGGCACAGGUGUCUGCCCCCUCUUUAAAAUCGAUCUACACACAUCCACGCACAUGCGACCCCGAGGAAACGAAACCCACUCUAGAAAACGCGACCUUGGCCGCACCUAAAGCAGCCAGCCGUGAGUGCAGACCCCUUGGCCAGCGUGGCGCAGUGGCCCUGAGCAGUAGUGGCAUGUGUGUAGAUCAAGUCGGAUCUAGUCCAGCUCGGUUCAUUAGCGAUCCAUGUAAUCUGACGUCAUCUUGUCUCGAAGUCUCUUUUUUUGGCCCAGGCCUUGAAGAAUACACUGUGACUUAAGAAGCCUUACCACGCAGUAACUAAAGCUUUAGGAUGACUGUAUUCGAGGAGUGCCGUGUGUUGCAUGCAGCUACCCGUAGGAAGACUUCGCGCAUAUCACUAAUAAACCUGAAGUCGUGAUGAAAA